ACUGCUGCCGACGCCGCCGACCCUGCCGACGCCCGCGGGAGACGUCACCCGGACGCGACGACGCUCUUCCCCGCCCCGACGUGGCAGCGCUACCCAGUCAGGCGAGGUGCUGCCUGCGCGUGGGCGGGACGCAUGCGCGUAGGGAGCACGUAGUGCGCGUGGGAGGCUCCGCCUUUUCGGUCCUGGGAACCCGCGCCCCCUGCCGGUGCCCUCCCCGCCCGGCCCUAGCUCUCUCGCCUUCUCGCCCGCCCGGCGCUGGCCCUGCUGGAUCCUGCGCGCCGGGGACUGGGGGCUGGCAGUGCAGACCGAACCCGGGGCCGAGGGGCUUCUCCACAGAGCCGCCUGGGGCUCGGUGGGGGGCGCUCAGCUCGACCCCAGCUAAGGGAGCACUAGGAAGUGCGGGCGUCCCCUUCCCUGCACCCUUGCGGGGCGGGAACCGUCGACCUAGAAGAAAAAAAAAGCUGAGGCAAACUUGAUAUAAGUAGAGAGGUUAUUUGGGCCAAGUUUGAAGAUUGCAACCCGGGAGCAUAGCUUCAAGUUGCCCUGAACAUAGGAUUUGCAACAGUGACAAAGGUGAGGCCAGAGAAGUGACAAGACAGAUGCCAGUCCAGCAGGUGGGCAUGUCCAGAAAGUGCAGCCUCAGGACACGGUCUGGGAACAAAGACUGCUGGAGAGUUGGAAGCUGGCAAGAGGCUCUCAGCUGUGAAGUACCUGGGGUGGGGGAGAAGUGGUCGGAGAAAGCAGAGCCCAGCCCGUCUUCCUGUUGGAGGCAUGUGACCCCUGGAGGACAAGCAUGAAACGCCAUAGGGCUCCCCCAGGUGCUGGAAUUAUGGCACCUUGCAGCUUCUUCUCCACGAGUUUUAACAAGCAUGCGUACUUUUGUAAGUGGUGAGUGUAACGGAGGUUCACAGAUGCACUCCGCUUUGGAAACCAGUGCACUCUUGCCCAGGCCCGGUGAGACUCUGACGACGAUGUGUCUAACCUCUGUGUCUAACGGGGGUGUGGGCUCUCCCUCCUCUGGCGACCAUGAGGACCACCCCGGCAGGACAAGGUGUGCAGAGAACUAGCAUGGUCCCUGGCACGUAGCCCCUGCCCAGUGACUGGCAGAUGAGAAGCUCCAUUGUCGCCCCAGGCGAGUAUGGGGCACAGGCGCCUCCUUGGGUUGUCUGCCCUCCCGGGAGCCCCAGGGUGCCCAGGCGGGCCUCAGCUGAGUCCAGGCCUCGGGGACAGUCCGUGCAGCCCCUCCUGGGGCUGGGGGCGGGCACUUGUCCCAGCCACGUUUCUGCUGACUGAGCAGCCUUCUUCAUGAGCUCACGCCUUUCCAGAGAAAUCCCUUAAUGCCUCCAUUCUGCUGGUGGCAUAUAUAGGGAGGGCUCGGCCUUGGCUCCACACUGCGCUGCCCAGAGGCCCCGCUGACUCCUGCCAGCCUCCAGGUCCCCGUGGUACCAAAGCUGAACAUGGAUGUGACCAUCCAGCACCCCUGGUUCAAGCGCACCCUGGGGCCCUUCUACCCCAGCCGGCUGUUCGACCAGUUUUUCGGCGAGGGCCUUUUUGAGUAUGACCUGCUGCCCUUCCUGUCGUCCACCAUCAGCCCCUACUACCGCCAGUCCCUCUUCCGCACCGUGCUGGACUCCGGCAUCUCUGAGGUUCGAUCCGACCGGGACAAGUUCGUCAUCUUCCUCGAUGUGAAGCACUUCUCCCCGGAGGACCUCACCGUGAAGGUGCAGGACGACUUUGUGGAGAUCCACGGAAAGCACAACGAGCGCCAGGACGACCACGGCUACAUUUCCCGUGAGUUCCACCGCCGCUACCGCCUGCCGUCCAACGUGGACCAGUCGGCCCUCUCUUGCUCCCUGUCUGCCGAUGGCAUGCUGACCUUCUGUGGCCCCAAGAUCCAGACUGGCCUGGAUGCCACCCACGCCGAGCGAGCCAUCCCCGUGUCGCGGGAGGAGAAGCCCACCUCGGCUCCCUCGUCCUAAGCAGGCAUUGCCUCGGCUGGCUCCCCUGCAGCCCUGGCCCAUCAUGGGGGGAGCACCCUGAGGGCGGGGUGUCUGUCUUCCUUUGCUUCCCUUUUUUCCUUUCCACCUUCUCACAUGGAAUGAGGGUUUGAGAGAGCAGCCAGGAGAGCUUAGGGUCUCAGGGUGUCCCAGACCCCGACACCGGCCAGUGGCGGAAGUGACCGCACCUCACACUCCUUUAGAUAGCAGCCUGGCUCCCCUGGGGUGCAGGCGCCUCAACUCUGCUGAGGGUCCAGAAGGAGGGGGUGACCUCCGGCCAGGUGCCUCCUGACACACCUGCAGCCUCCCUCCGCGGCGGGCCCUGCCCACACCUCCUGGGGCGCGUGAGGCCCGUGGGGCCGGGGCUUCUGUGCACCUGGGCUCUCGCGGCCUCUUCUCUCAGACCGUCUUCCUCCAACCCCUCUAUGUAGUGCCGCUCUUGGGGACAUGGGUCGCCCAUGAGAGCGCAGCCCGCGGCAAUCAAUAAACAGCAGGUGAUACAAGCAA